GCUUCCGGUGUCCCCUACAGUCAUGGCUGCCGCCGUCGCUGCUGCCGGUGCAGGGGAACCCCAGUCCCCGGACGAAUUGCUCCCGAAAGGCGACGCGGAGAAGCCUGAGGAGGAGCUGGAGGAGGACGACGAUGAGGAGCUAGAUGAGACCCUGUCGGAGAGACUAUGGGGCCUGACGGAGAUGUUUCCGGAGAGGGUCCGGUCCGCGGCCGGAGCCACUUUUGAUCUUUCCCUCUUUGUGGCUCAGAAAAUGUACAGGUUUUCCAGGGCAGCCUUGUGGAUUGGGACCACUUCCUUUAUGAUCCUGGUUCUUCCCGUUGUCUUUGAGACGGAGAAGUUGCAAAUGGAGCAACAGCAGCAACUGCAGCAGCGGCAGAUACUUCUAGGACCUAACACAGGGCUCUCAGGAGGAAUGCCAGGGGCUCUACCCUCACUUCCUGGAAAGAUCUAGAUUGUUAUUGCUGUUUGAGCUGUCUCAGUGGGAUAAGUUUGAAAUUCAAGUGUUUGAACUGCUGAUAAUUUGGAUUUUUUUUUUUUUUUAACUUUGGCACAUUGAUCUAUCUAAACCUGGUGGGGAGAAUUAUCCCCACAUUGUCUCAUGGAAAGACUCAACUUGCAACUGUGCCCUCCACACUAUCCUUACUUCUGUCUCCACUCUGAUACCAGAGUGCAGCCAUGCAGAUGGUUAUUCCAGCUCUGGUCACCCGACUCCUUUCACCAAAUUGCUCCUAACUGGAAGAUCUCACUUUCCCCUUGUGGGGUAGGAACCGAUGCCAGUGGGAGGGAUGUGCCCCUGACCAUUAACGACUGUUUUUUUUUUUUUUUUUUAAAGAAUGGAGUUGUUGGGGCAGGACAUGCACACAAUGUGAAACAGACAAAAUGCAUUACACCUGUAGUGUAAAGUGGCCACUAUGAAUCCCUAUGUAUGAGAGGAGGGAGGCAGGCUGCAGCUUCAGCCACAGAAUGGGGACUAUGGAAGACAGCAGGAGCUCAUUUCCUCUGCACAUUUUGGCUGUUAGACCUGUGUGUGUGUUUAAAAAAAGAGAAGUCAGUGCUCACUUUUUGUAUUUAAAUAUUAAAAAUGAUUCCAACUGAAAGUGUCAUCCUAAGUACCUUGAAAUGAGACCACGUCAGAGACAUGUACUGCCCCUCACAUUUUCUCACCUAAACCAGCAGCACCUCCAUCUUAACAGCCAUAGGCCCAAAUUGUUUCCAAGUGAAAAUUCAUUUUUAGCCAAGUACUUCAUAGCAAUCUUUGCCCUGAAUUUAGGCAGUCACUUUGAGAUCCAUCAGCCUAAAACAAAGGAUUGGGUCUAUGUACUUCUUUAGUCUAUAAUGACACUGUGUAAUUAUAAAGUAUUUGUAGGGAAUAACAUAGUACUGAUUUCUGGGGAAUAGGGGAGGGGGACAGAAUUUUUUUUUUUUUUUUUUUGCCUGAGAUCAGGUCUCACUGGAGUACAGUGGUGUCGUUUGGGUUCACUGCAACCUCUUACCUCCCCUCCAACUUGGCCUCCUGGGUAGCUAAGACUACAGGUACACGCCACCGUGCCCAGCUAGUUUCUUUUAUUUUUGGUAGAGUCAGGGUUUCGCCUUGUUGCCCCAGAUAGUCUUGAACUCCUGAGUUCUAGCCAUCCACCCGCCUCUGGCCCCUCAAAGUGCUGGGAUUAUAGGCGUCACCCACCACGCCCAGCCAGAGUAAGCCUUUUGUGUGUUUAUCAGAUCAACCAACACUACAAUCUAGGUGGUACUGUUCCCAUUUUACAGAAGAGGAAACAGCCACAGAAAGGUAAUUGCUCAAGGCUGCAGAGUUAAGUGCUAGACCUGGAUUCAAAUCCAGGCAGUCCAGCUACAGAACACUGCUGCUGUGCGCUCGGGAUGGUGGGGCUGGGCCCAGGCCCGCUGGGUAUACAUGAUCUUUCACUUGUUAACUAGGGAAAAACACUAGUCACCAGUGUGGUACAAACUUGUACUUAGGUGGAUUCUUCAAAUUGUCAAGAUUAGUUUUUAUAAAUUAAAAUAGACUGAAAAAUG